AGGUAGAGGUUGAGACUCCACUGAAUAAACUCUAGGUUCCCAUUUCUUUCAGCCAGAUCCUCCCAGGGAAUCACUACAGGCUGGUUAGCCAAAAAGUCCUGAUUUUCUGCUCAAUAGAGGUCCUUACUGGAAGGCAGCAUGUCCAAUGUUACCUUGAGAAAAAUGUCUCCCACAGGAAAUGAGAUGAAGAGCACCACUCAGGGAACCACACGGAAGCAGCAGGAUUUUCACGAGGUGAACAAAAGAAGAACUUUCUUACAGGAUAACAGUUGGAUAAAGAAACGCCCUGAAGAAGAAAAAGAUGAAAAUUACGGUAGGGUGGUGCUCAACCGACAUAAUUCCCAUGAUGCAUUGGACAGGAAAGUAAAUGAGAGAGAUGUGCCAAAAGCUACAAUUAGUCGGUACAGUUCUGAUGACACUUUGGACAGGAUCUCAGACAGAAAUGAUGCUGCUAAAACAUAUAAGGCCAAUACCUUGGAUAACCAACUAACCAAUAGGAGCAUGUCCAUGUUUAGAUCACUGGAAGUAACAAAGUUGCAACCUGGCGGUUCAUUGAAUGCCAACACCUCCAACACCAUAGCAUCCACUUCUGCUACUACUCCUGUAAAGAAGAAGAGGCAGUCCUGGUUUCCACCGCCCCCUCCAGGUUACAAUGCCUCCUCGAGCACAGGAACCAGGAGACGGGAACCAGGUGUUCACCCUCCAAUACCUCCAAAGCCCAGUUCUCCUGUUUCUUCUCCUAACCAGCUGAGACAGGAUAAUAGGCAGAUACAUCCACCUAAACCAGGUGUAUAUACAGAAACCAACAGAUCUGCUGAAAGAAAUAUAAGGAGUCAGGAUCUUGAUAACAUCGUCAAAGUGGCCACUUCACUUCAGAGAAGUGACAAAGGUGAAGAAUUGGAUAAUCUCAUCAAAAUGAACAAAAGCUUGAAUAGGAAUCAAGGUCUUGAUAGUCUCUUCAGAGCAAAUCCAAAGGUAGAAGAAAGAGAGAAAAGAGCCAAAAGCCUUGAAAGUCUCAUCUAUAUGAGUACCCGGACAGAUAAAGAUGGCAAAGGAAUCCAAAGCCUUGGAAGUCCGAUUAAAGUUAAUCAAAGGACUGACAAAAAUGAGAAAGGAAGACAAAAUCUCGAAUCUGUUGCUAAAGUGAAUGCCAGGAUGAAUAAAACGAGCAGAAGAAGUGAAGACCUUGAUAAUGCUACUGAAGUAAAUCCCAAAGGACAUGAAAAUACCACUGGAAAAAAAGACCUUGAUGGGCUUAUUAAAGUGGAUCCUGAAACAAAUAAAAAUAUUACGAGGGGCCAGAGCCUUGAUAAUCUCAUCAAAGUGACCCCUGAAGUAAAGAGAAGUAACCAAGGUUCCAAAGACCUUAAUAACUUCAUCAAAGUGUAUCCAGGAACAGAAAAAAGUACUGAAGGGGGCCAAAGUCUCGACAGCCUCAUUAAAGUGACUCCUGAAAGAAACAGAACUAACCAAGGGAACCAAGACUUGGAAAAUCUUAUCAAAGUGAUCCCUUCAGCAAACAAAAGCAGUGAACAAGGUCUUGAUGAACAUAUUAAUGUCAGCCCCAAAGCUGUCAAAAACACUGAUGGAAAACAAGAUCUUGAUAAACUCAUCAAGGUGAAUCCUGAAAUUUUCACAAACAACCAAAGAAACCAAGAUCUUGCUAACCUCAUCAAAGUAAAUCCUGCAGUAAUCAGAAACAAUCAGAGCCAAGACUUGGACAAUCUUAUUAAAGUGAAACCUUCAGCUCUUAGAAACACUAAUCGAGACCAGAACCUGGAAAAUUUAAUUGAAGUAAAUUCUCAUGUGUCUGAAAACAAGAAUGGAAGCUCUAACACUGGAGCCAAGCAGGCAGGACCACAGGAUACUGUUGUGUACACAAGGACAUAUGUGGAGAAUAGUAAAUCACCCAAGGAUGGAUAUCAGGAGAAUAUCUCUGGAAAAUACAUACAAACUGUUUAUUCAACUUCUGAUAGGUCUGUCAUUGAAAGAGAUAUGUGCACUUACUGCCGAAAACCCUUGGGUGUAGAAACUAAAAUGAUUUUAGAUGAAUUACAAAUUUGCUGCCAUUCUACUUGCUUUAAGUGUGAAAUAUGCAAGCAGCCUUUGGAAAAUCUACAAGCGGGUGAUAGUAUUUGGAUUUAUAGACAGACAAUACACUGUGAACCUUGCUACUCUAAAAUUAUGGCAAAGUGGAUUCCAUAACUCUGGCACAAGGAAAUCAAGAUGAAAAGCACUCAUUAAGGAAUUAAAGUUACAAGUUUUAUCUUAAUAAUAUGUAAUCUAGAAAAGCUUUCACAUUGAAGAUCAACUCUUGUACAAAAUUAACAAUUCUGUUAUUGCAUAAGUAAUCUAAUUGUCUUCAAUAAGGUCACACACAUAAAAAGAGCCAUCUGGUCUCUGGCUAGAGUUAGCAAUAAAAAGUUCAAAUGGUUCCAGAUUCCAGUGUCAAAGGAGUGAUGCAUUACACUCCAGCCAGGUCCAUCCCUGCUCCGUAUGUUGGCUGUGAGUGGUGGUUUCCAUUUAAACCAAGUUUCUCAUUUCUUCACCUUUUUUUCUCUAAGAAUUUGGAUUCGUAGACAUUGACAUCCCGAAGAACUGUCAAGGAAGCAAGAUAUGCUUUCUUCAUCUGCAAAAGAAAUACUAACAACAAUUUUCUUAUACAGUUUGGCAGAAAGAUGUUAACAUAAAAAGUUUAUAUACCUCAAAAAUCACUAAACUUUCCAGAUCUCUGUCCUAUUAUUUGUAACACAAGGGGCAUUGGAUAAAAUGAUUUCUAGGGUUCCUUUUGCUUCCCAAAUUCUCUGAUUCUAAAGCAGUUUUUAGAAUCAUUAGCUCUUUGGAAACAUAUAUGCAUACAUGUUUGUUAAGCCUAUUGAACUAGGUAGGACAUAUAAACAAUUUAAUUUUAGUGUCAUUGUUUAAUCACAGACUUAGUGUUUGAAAACUGUGUUUUAAAAACAGAAACAGAUUGAUGGGUAACAGGUAAAAUAUGACAUGUAUAGCUUACAUGUUAUUAUUUGUUAAAUUUUCUUUGUAUACAUUUCAAAAUCUGGGUAUACUUAUAAUCCAUUAGAAGUAAUGGUUAUGGACUAAAAAGAUAUGUUCUUUAGUAUGUUAUAUAUACUCAUAUUACAUAGCAGUAUGUUUACAAAAGGCUUAUAAAAAUAAAAUGAACUAUCAGUUACAUAGAA